AUUCGCGCCGCCGCCGCCCGCCAUGCGCUUCCGCUUUGGGGUGGUGGUGCCACCCGCCGUGGCCGGCGCCCGGCCGGAGCUGCUGGUGGUGGGGUCGCGGCCCGAGCUGGGGCGUUGGGAGCCGCGCGGUGCCGUCCGCCUGAGGCCGGCCGGCACCGCGGCGGGCGACGGGGCCCUGGCCCUGCAGGAGCCGGGCCUGUGGCUCGGGGAGGUGGAGCUGGCGGCCGAGGAGGCGGCGCAGGACGGGGCGGAGCCGGGCCGCGUGGACACGUUCUGGUACAAGUUCCUGAAGCGGGAGCCGGGAGGAGAGCUCUCCUGGGAAGGCAAUGGACCUCAUCAUGACCGUUGCUGUACUUACAAUGAAAACAACUUGGUGGAUGGUGUGUAUUGUCUCCCAAUAGGACACUGGAUUGAGGCCACUGGGCACACCAAUGAAAUGAAGCACACAACAGACUUCUAUUUUAAUAUUGCAGGCCACCAAGCCAUGCAUUAUUCAAGAAUUCUACCAAAUAUCUGGCUGGGUAGCUGCCCUCGUCAGGUGGAACAUGUAACCAUCAAACUGAAGCAUGAAUUGGGGAUUACAGCUGUAAUGAAUUUCCAGACUGAAUGGGAUAUUGUACAGAAUUCCUCAGGCUGUAACCGCUACCCAGAGCCCAUGACUCCAGACACUAUGAUUAAACUAUAUAGGGAAGAAGGCUUGGCCUACAUCUGGAUGCCAACACCAGAUAUGAGCACCGAAGACGAAGAGGCUGAGGCAUGAAAAAGUUAUUGCCCAUGUCAUAGAACUAAAAAGAGGCCCAUUCUGAAUUUCAAGGCUGGCAGUCGGACCCAGAACAUUGCUCCAGACAGCAACUUUACCAGCUAUGAAGCUUCUCCCUGCAUUCUUACACAGACGCUUCAGGCAGGUUCUUCAGACCCAUGCAAUUUCAACCCCUUAUGUUCAUGAUCAUCUGGAGUUAGGCAGAGCCUACAAAUUGCAAGGGAAGUAGCUUGUCUCCCCAAGAGUGAAUGGUCUGCAAGAUAAAAAACCAUGAGGACCACAGGAAAUCUACGUUUCUGGACCUUGCCCACCUCAGCCCUUUAUGGAUCUCAGGUGGUCCUCCUGGCCAGGCUGGGCCCCUUUGUUGAUCUGUGUCUGAGCUGAAUUGCCAUUGGGGAUGGGGUAUAAUGUUUGUUCCUGAAGGUGGAGAGAGCUGCUGACAGUCUGGUUAUUCCUCUUGGUAACCUGACCUAAGGAAGCAUGAUUUAGCUGUAAGAGCUCUGCCCUUCUUCAAGGAAGAAAAAAAGAAAAACUUCAUUUGCGAAGAUGCACAUUGGUUGAAUCCAGGUGAUAUUUACCUUGUCCAGCUGGUUUUCCUGGUUUCAAAACAGAGAAGAUAGUUAGGAUUUGAAGGACUGUAGCUUCCAGAGAGCAUUUUGAUGUUAGCAUCUCUGAAUCUGAUUUGACAGCAUUGUUAUCCUGUUGGAGAAUGAUGUGAGACGAGGCUGGGAGAAGUUAGGCUGCCAACUGUGCCACGCAUCCCCCGCCAUCCCAUCCCAACCCACACACUGAUUACCUGAAGGCUCUGCUGACAGAUAGUAAUUUGCUUGAUAGUUUGGGACUCUGCAGAAGCCUGAGGGAAAACUGUAUCCCCAAGGACCCAUUGUAGUUGUGUUCACGAACCUUUUUUGCGGUCAGUGGGUUACCAGGUCACAGUCGUAACUGUUAGUGCAGUAGCAUAGCUUCUUUCAGGCUGAGACAGUGCAGUGGCAUUUGAGCUGCAAAAUGCAAGCUUCCACGUGAUAAAGGCCCAGCUGUAAGACCGACUAAUGGAUUUCUUUGGCUUGGCCUAACCUGGGGGUGUAAUCUAAGGGUUAAUAACCACUUCUGAGUGGCAGGGGAACUUUUUACCAAUAGACCAAUGUCUGUGGCUCACAGUAUUAGCCCAAUGAACACAUAGAUUAAUCAGCUGAAUAUUUUUAGAACUCUAGAGAAAAACCCAGUUGGAAGUGUUUUGAGCUGCAGCAUAAUGCUCUCAGUUGAAGUCUGAGAAAGAAGACAGUUUGUUAGGCUUGACUGUCACCGCUAGUUGUCACAGACCUGUUAUAAUCAAUCGUGUGAUCGAUCCUUACUCUUGCAUGCUUUUGUCAUAUGUGGAAUGGUGGUGUAGAUUUCUUUUUUUAAAAAAUCUUUUAUAAACAUUUUGGUUUGUGUCUUUCACCUAGGGAAUGAAAAUCUGCCAAAUCUAACACUCACCUGAACAAAACAAAAUGAAACAAAUCUGCUCGUUAAAAUUUUCUUUGCAUAGAAGGUAUUCAGGUUGUGUUUUGACCUCUGUCACUGCAGCACUAUUUAUAACAAAUGUCUACCCUUGCCUCCCAAAUGAGUUCACAGGCUUCAUGAAGUCCUCAGCUACCCCUCUGUUGUCAAAGUCUGACUUCCUUUCCCUUGCUCAACACACUGAUUUCGGCUCUCCCAUUGCACGGAAAUGCUGACCUUGGAGCCAAGACAACUGGGCUAAAGCCUUGUCACCACUGGGUAGCUGGGAGGAUAUCGGCAGGCUAGUUCCUGCAUUAAGAAAAUGAGGAUAGUAAUUUCCACCUUACAGGACUAUAACAGUAGAAUAAGAUAAUUGAUAUGAAAGGGCUUUGAAAAUCACAAAGUUGGAAUUGUAGGAUUAGUUCCAAGUCUUUAAGUUUCUACCAAAGGAUGUUAUAGAUAAUGUAGAUCCUAUCUAUAUUACACUUCAAAGAUGGAAAAAAAUAUGCCCCCCACAUAAUAUAUUCAUCAUAUAUCUGCUCCUGGAGUAAGAAAGGAAAGUGUGUGUGUGUGUGUGUGUGUGUGUGUGUGAGAGAGAGAGAGAGAGAGAGAGAAAGGCUGAAAGCUGCAGAUUUCUUUCAGGAUCAACCUUGGAUAAAGCAUAUCUUUAGGGCCUUUUGACCCCUCUCUUUUAUCUCAGGCCCUAAUACCUCAGGCUACUUGACUUACCUGCCCAAAUGCUCUACCUCUCCCUCUCCUCACAACCUUGGCUGGCUCAAUAGUGCUUUCAGGAAGCUUUUGGUUGGUCCAGAGUCAGAUUAGCCUGGAGCUGGUGUGAACCACAGGUUAGGCUAGAAGUGCUUAGUAGUGUCUCAGAUCAAAUAGGCUUUUAUUGCUGUUUUUCUAGUCUUGUGUUUAUUCAUGGACUUAAUGAGUGUGUAUGGAGCAUCUACUGAGAACUAGGGCCUGUAUUAAAUUACAGAGUCAGAAACUCAGAGGGUAGAAUGUCUUGUUUGACCUGCAAAGGAUUUACAGUUUUUCAACUUAGUUGUCAGCAUUUAAAGUUUGGAAUACUUUAUGUUAAAAGAUCUGGAUUUCUGUCUUUUCUUGAGGUUUUAUUGUUUUUAAGAAUGGAAAUGUCUUAUCAAAUUAAAUUCUAUGUGGAGCCUA